ACACCCGCCUCGCUGUCUUGGAGUCUUGAUCUGUCGUCGGCGGGUCGCUGGCACAGGACUAAACAUGGCUGAGGCUGGGCUCCAGCCAGAUCUGGCUGGGGACAGCACCGCGUGGGCCCAGGAUCCACCCAGAGCAGGCAGGCCUUGCUGGGGCCCCAGUCAAGUCCACUUCCAGUGAGGAGAGCCAGCCGGGAGGUCAGUGCCAGAGCUCUGGUGGAGCCCAGACCCUGCCUUCCCUGAGGGCCGCCCCUGUCGCCGCCCUGGGGUCCCUGUCCUCCUAUCCUGACUCCUGCCCCAGGGCCACCACCCCUGAACUGUGCCCUGGGGCCCCCACCCUCCACCUGGCCGACUCCAGCUCUGGGCCUGUCAGUCCACCUGGGUCCUCUCUGGGCCCUGAGUGCCUGGACCCUCUGUGCCAAGCACCAGCAAGCAAAGGGGAUGACCUUGGGCACCCCCAAGGUGCUGAGACUACAGCCAGUGAGCCCCUGCUGGGGGCCAAAGCCAUGGAGGGUGCCUGGGCCCUUCCAACCUGGAAGGAGGAGGGGAGAGAGCAGGCAGCAGGGCAGGGGGAAGAGGAGGAGUGCCCGAUCUGCACAGAGCCCUACGGGCCCAGAGAGCGCCGCCUGGCCCUGCUGAACUGUAGCCACGGCCUGUGUGUGGGCUGCCUGCACAGGCUGCUGGGCUCGGCCUCCAGUGCCGACCUGGGCCGGGUGCGCUGCCCGCUGUGCCGCCAGAAGACGCCCGUGCUGGAAUGGGAGAUCUGCCGGCUACAGGAGGAGCUGCUACAGGCCGACGGGCCCUCACGCCAGCCCCGCCGAGAGGCCCCUGCAUCCUAUCACCGCAACCCUGGGCCCUGGGGCUCCCUGGAGCACCGCUACCAGCUGCGCUUCCUGGCAGGGCCCGUGGGCGGCCGGGGCUGCCUGCCCUUCCUGCCCUGUCCACCCUGCCUGGGUGCCCGGCUCUGGACCCUGCGGGAGCGGGGACCCUGUGCCCGCCGCCUGGCGCUGCUGAGCCUGCUGGCCCUUGAGCUUCUGGGGCUGCUGCUGGUCUUCACGCCGCUCCUGCUGCUGGGACUGCUCUUCGUGCUCCUGGACCGCUCUGGCCGCUGAGCAGAGCCCAGGACAGCCCCGCCGCCAACAGGCCAGGGGGCCCAGACUGGCCCACGUCCCCAUGCCUGGGUGCUGUGAGGCCUGAUGACCAGGCUGGAAAAACCCAAGGUUGGGUCCAGGGCAGUGGCCUUCAAUCAAGACCUCCCAUUGCUGAACCCACAACCAGGGCUACCCAGAGGCCUGACCCUGCCAGAGUCCAUGGCUGCACUGCUGCCCAGACACUAGCUGAACCCAAGGACACCAGCGCCCAAGGACAGCUCCUGGAGGAGGCCAGCCCAGCAGGAAAGUCUGUGAGCAGGACCCCAUUCACCCUGCGGCAGACGGGCACCGUACUGGCCACGGGCUGACGCCGGCCACACUUCCCCUCCGAGGGCCAGCUGAGCACAGCAGGCAUGAAAGCAAACAGAGAUACAGCAGUGAGUCAGUUCCUUGGAGAGGGCAGGGACUCCGCCCACCCUGUGUUCAGAUAAGGGCCAGUGUGUGUCCCUGAAGGUCAGGCCAGCCGGGGGAGGGGUCCAUGCUGCGAAAAUUCAGCCUGCAAAGGCUCCUCUCCCCACUUGAUCAGGCCCAGACCAGGUGGGGGUUGGCGCUGGCCUGUGUUGCAGGGGACAAGGGCCCACCCAGGCCUUGGAACAUAAGCUCUGCCCCUGCACACCCUCAUGUCACCACACCUGGGAUGGAGACAUCAGGUGGCCCAGCGAGAGAUGGAGGACUGAUCCUGGAACGUGAAGCAGCUUUCAAUAAACCAGCUCCUGGGGA